UUGCUCAUCUGCCUGAACUCACUGAGGGUUGGGACUGUUUCACACAUGCAGUAUUGGCACUUAGACUUAAUGUUGAAUGAAGGGGAGGCAUUUUAAAAUUCACAUCAAAAAACUGUUAUUCUUUAAAAAAAAUACUAAUCUACAAGGUCACUUCCCCUCCAAGCAUGACGUCUACCUUUACUUUCUGAUAAUCAUGAUCGGCUUGUGGGGAUCAAGAUUACUCAGGAUUAAAUUCUGGCCCCAUCUUGAGCCGUCAUGGAAACUUGGGGAAGCUACUUAACUUCUCCAUCUAGAUUGAUUCUGCAAAAUCCGUAAAAUGGAAUGGUUUCUGGGGGUUAAAUUAGUAUACCACUGUUGGAAUACUGUCAGGCUUGCCAGAUAUUUACUGUUCAUCUUCAUCAAAUGAGGACAGUGGUAUCCCACUAUAUGGUUUUCAAUUUUGUGUAAGAAAAACGUGCUUUAUGCAUUGUUAGUAAAAGAAAUAUCUGAAUAUCCCUGCCAUGGAAGAAAGAAACAGAGGGAGAAAAGAGAGUUGGUGCCCAAUGGGGAGCAAACUGACUUGCUGCCUGGGCCCCAGCGGGGGCCUCAACUGUGACUGCUGCAGGCCAGAUGUGGGACCCUGCCAUGAGUGUGAGAUUCCUGAGACUGUGGCAGCCACAGCACCAGCAUCCACCACUGCAAAGCCUGCCAAAUUGGAUUUGAAAGCUAAGAAGGCCCAACUCAUGCAGUACCUCAGCCUCCCGAAGACGCCGAAGAUGCUGAAGAUGUCCAAAGGUUUGGACGCCCGCUCCAAGCGCUGGUUAAAAAUAAUAUGGAGACGGCACGGGAUUUGGCCUCUAGAAAAUAUAGGUCCCACUGAAGAUGUGCAGGCGUCUGCACACGGCGGUGUGGAGGAGAAUAUGACAUCAGAUAUUGAAAUACCUGAGGCCAAGCACGACCACCGUCCCACUGAAGAUGUGCAGGUGUCUGCACACGGCGGUGUGGAGGAGAAUAUAACGUCAGAUAUUGAAAUAUCUGAGGCCAAGCACGACCACCAUUUGGUCGAAGAUCUCAGUGAAAGCCUAUCUGUCUGUCUUGAAGACUUCAUGACAUCGGAUCUCAGUGAAAGCCUAUCUGUCUCUCUUGAAGACUUCAUGACAUCAGGUCUCAGUGAAAGCCUAUCUGUCUCUCUUGAAGACCUCAUGACACCGGAGAUGGCAAAGGAGAGAUAUGAAGAUUACCUCUGCUGGGUUAAGAUGGCACGGUCUCGGCUCAAUGAACCCAUCAGCAGCCAGGUUCUAGGACUUCUCCGGCUUUAGUGUUCCAAGUAGCUGGGAUUACAGACGCCUGCCAUCACGCCCAGCUCAAAUCAUUUUAUGAAUGCAUAUUUCCAUCUGGGUGAAAAAAAAAUCACAAGCCUCUCUCUCUUCCUACUGAGCACCUGUGAACAGUGACCUGCAGUUUGUGGCUGCAGCCAGUCCUCUUGCAGCCUGGUGUUCUUACAUUUCAUUCUGAGGCUCACAUUCUCAGUCACCAUGCAGAAGAACACCCGCCCCAUCCUGGGUCAUUACAGAGUGGGUCAAUCCAUCUGCUGCAUCUGAAGAGCUGGGUCCAGCUUCUACAGUGAAUCCAUAUAUUUCUGUAUUUCCUGGAUAAGGAAGAGCAAAGGAGCUGAGCUGGUGGAGGAAGAAGAACUAAUAUUAACUGACUCCUUAUUUUGUGCUAGUACUGUGCUAGUUACAUAUUUUAUCUCAUGUAAUUCUUACCAAACUGUAAGGGGGUUUCGGAGUGAUGGAGACAAUAUUGAUGUUAUCUCCAUUUUAGGGUGAGAAAAUAAAGGCUCAGAAAUGUUA